GGUCUCCAGGGCCAGGAGACCAAGGCUGGCCUGUGAUGUUGUGUCAGGUGCUCAAGGAAUCCCAGAAGUGUACAAGACGGUGUGUAGUUUUCGCUCUUUUCUUCAUGUCAUGGAUUGCUGGCUUGAGUUUUAAUUAGGUUGCAUGAAAGUGCAAUUUGUUGGGAACUUUAAUCAUCUUCCACUGGGGAGCCUUGCUGGGCUGGUUUAUUUUCAUCCUGCUCCUCCCUGGGUGUGAAGACGGGGUUGAGGGACAUUUUAGUACCUGUCUGCUCUCUCCUGCUUUGCUGGCCUUGAUAACCACAUUUUCUAACACAAAACUUGGGACAUGAGAGCCUGACUUCUGCCAAUGUUGUGGAGUUUUUUCCUAUUUGUUAAUUUGAUUAAACUGAAAGGUUUAUGAAAAUAUAGAAGUUAAACAACAUUGGACACUUAAUACAUUUAAUGAGCUUCCUUUAUUUGGAAAGAACCACACUUCACAAGCCAGGGGUCCCUUCAGACAGUCUUGGGAGUCGGAUUGCUGGGAGGUGAGGUCCUGAUCCAGGAACUUUGAGUUAAUGGUGGUCAUUAUGAUGCUGGUGGCAGCUGUGUUCCCUCUGUGUACAGAUGAAUUCAUCCAACCUCAUAACAAACCCAGGAGGGAGGUCCUCUCACAACUUCAGCUCAGAGGCGAGGACACUGAGGCCCAGGGCAGUGAGGCCCCUUUGCCAGGCUGCCAAGUGACUGGGCCAGGGUGUCACCCAAGCCAGGCUGGCUUGAGGGUUCAUCCUCAUGACCCCUGCACUGCCGCUGUUGUGCUGCAGUUAGUGUUUUUCAAGUGGUCUCUGAGUUUUGAGAAGCGACAGGCUGCAUACUUGGCUCUUGACCCCCAUGACCUCGGUGGCACUGUGCCUCAGCCCCAGGUUGUCAAUUUGAAAUUGGGUGGACUUCACAGGCACUGGCCUCCAGGGGCCCACGGAGGAGUGUUCGGAGGGGUUUCCACCCAACACGCCUAGUGGGGCUCUGGGUCCCGGCCCCAGAGGCUGAGCCCUACUAUCCUUCCCUGAGCUGAGGCCCCCACCCCUUUCAUACCUCAAGCUCAUCCUGGGCAGUGGCUGGGCCCUGGGCCAUUCUGGACAAGGCAGGGUGGUCCUACCCUGAGACCUACCUGGUACAAAGACCUGGGAUUGCAGUGAGAAAAAAGCUUUUACCAAAUAGCCAUCCAGCCGGGUUGAACUCUUCCCAAGCCCCCACCCCUCAACCAGCUUAUUACAUGCAAGUUUUAAGCUAUCCUUGCCUGGAGCCUUCUCUUGCCUUUUGUCAAUUGCUGUAAUUUUCUGGUAAAGCUAUAUCAACAAAAUGGCAACCAUUCCUGCCUCCCACUGUUUAUCCCUCCUUCCCCUAGGAAACCCUCCCACAUUCCCUGUUUUCAGGAUCUUGGUCCCGUGCAGGACUCCAGGCAGCACCCACAGAACCCUGGAGUGGCACAGGCCUCGGUGCCUACUCUACAGCUUUCCUGAGCACUUCUCAGAUUCCACACAAAGGGUCCUUGGGACCCAGCAUAGCCUGCAGGCAAGAACACCUGGUCAGAACUUCCUCUUGGGGCAGGGAUGGUACCAGUAGUGCCUGGUGAAAAGCUUGGUGCUUUAGAUACCACCUUAAUCCCCAGUUCAUACAAUGGAGGCUUGGCAUAGUGUAGGGCAAGAGGGAGCUUUAUCCAUGCAGCAGAUAGUAGCUGAGGUGUUUUCAGAGGUGGAUUAAGUGGCAGUUGAUGGGAAACUGUCAUUUUUACAGUCCAAGAAUGUGGCUGUUUUUUAUGGUGGUUAAGAAUUCAGGUGUAUCUGGAAAAGCAGGUGAAAAAGUAAAUGCUAAUCUAGUUCAGUUGACAGUUCCGUUGCAGUAGAAUCCUCUUGUAGGGGGCAAUUUAGCAUAGAUCAGGACAGCCACCCUGAACAUGAACUUCAGGAUCAAAGCGACUUGGUGCAUAGAUGGAUGUGUGUUGGGAGUCCACAGUGUUCCUGGCUUCACUCUGGCAUCCAGAGUUGAUGUCCUCUUACGAAAGGAAGCAGAAUUUUUUUUUUAUAUGUGGGCUUGAGAUGGGAUAUUAAGUAGGUGGCUGAGGGUUUUACAUUAUUGCUCCAAGCUUAUGAAUAAUUUAGAGCUACAGUCUGGUUUGCCAGAACUCUCUUCUUGGAUUCCAGCCUCUUCCUUCCUGAGAAGGAUUCUGUGCUCGUAAACCACAGCCCUGGAGGUGGACUCGGGGGGGGCCUUUUGUCUCAUAGACUCUGGCUCGCUCGUCAAGUGGCCUUCCAGGGCAUUGCUUCCCAGCGACAGCACAUGGUGCUCACCACGGUCCUCACCAGCUCCUCCUCAGCCUUCCUUUAACCCUGUGUCCCCCUCUUAUCUCCUGCUUUGGGCACAGGAGGACAGGUGAAUGCGGAGGAAUGGGGGAGGUUCAGGGGAAAUAAGGGCAGAUGGGGAAAAACACACAUUUUCUAAGAAUCAACUGCACACUGUUGCACAGACACUCAUACAGCCUCCAGAUUUCAUGGCUCACUGGGGAAUGCUGGGCAGGAACAUGCCACAGGCACAGCGGGGCAGCACGCUCACCGGCCGGAGCCCAUGCUGGUGCUUGGGGCAGGGCCCUGCACUGAAUCCCCUUUGGGUGUCUGUGAGGCCUGUGGUCAGAAGUCCAUCUGUGGCCCUCACUGUAACAGUCUAGGGGCUGCUCCACCCAGAAACGUCCGUCCUCUGAGUGUCUGCUCUGAAGAGGAUAAGAAUUGGAAGAGUCUGCCGAAGGUGAAGGCCAUGGACUUCAUCACCUCCACAGCCAUCCUGCCCCUGCUGUUCGGCUGCCUGGGCGUCUUCGGCCUCUUCCGGCUGCUGCAGUGGGUGCGCGGGAAGGCCUACCUGCGGAAUGCUGUGGUGGUGAUCACAGGCGCCACCUCAGGGCUGGGCAAAGAAUGUGCAAAAGUCUUCUAUGCUGCGGGUGCUAAACUGGUGCUCUGUGGCCGGAAUGGUGGGGCCCUAGAAGAGCUCAUCAGAGAACUCACCGCUUCUCAUGCCACCAAGGUGCAGACACACAAGCCUUACUUGGUGACCUUCGACCUCACAGACUCUGGGGCCAUAGUUGCAGCAGCAGCUGAGAUCCUGCAGUGCUUUGGCUAUGUCGACAUACUUGUCAACAAUGCUGGGAUCAGCUACCGUGGUACCAUCAUGGACACCACAGUGGAUGUGGACAAGAGGGUCAUGGAGACAAACUACUUUGGCCCAGUUGCUCUAACGAAAGCACUCCUGCCCUCCAUGAUCAAGAGGAGGCAAGGCCACAUUGUCGCCAUCAGCAGCAUCCAGGGCAAGAUGAGCAUUCCUUUUCGAUCAGCAUAUGCAGCCUCCAAGCACGCAACCCAGGCUUUCUUUGACUGUCUGCGUGCCGAGAUGGAACAGUAUGAAAUUGAGGUGACCGUCAUCAGCCCCGGCUACAUCCACACCAACCUCUCUGUAAAUGCCAUCACCGCGGAUGGAUCUAGGUAUGGAGUUAUGGACACCACCACAGCCCAGGGCCGAAGCCCUGUGGAGGUGGCCCAGGAUGUUCUUGCUGCUGUGGGGAAGAAGAAGAAAGAUGUGAUCCUGGCUGACUUACUGCCUUCCUUGGCUGUUUAUCUUCGAACUCUGGCUCCUGGGCUCUUCUUCAGCCUCAUGGCCUCCAGGGCCAGAAAAGAGCGGAAAUCCAAGAACUCCUAGUACUCUGACCAGCCAGGGCCAGGGCAGAGAAGCAGCACUCUUAGGCUUGCUUACUCUACAAGGGACAGUUGCAUUUGUUGAGACUUUAAUGGAGAUUUGUCUCACAAGUGGGAAAGACUGAAGAAACACAUCUCGUGCAGAUCUGCUGGCAGAGGACAAUCAAAAACGACAACAAGCUUCUUCCCAGGGUGAGGGGAAACACUUAAGGAAUAAAUAUGGAGCUGGGGUUUAACACUAAAAACUAGAAAUAAACAUCUCAAACAGUAA